GCGCGCCCCGCACGCGCAUAACGGCUUGGCUUACCUGUAACGGGGGGAGCGGCAAGAGCAACGUGGGCACUUGGGGAGACUACGACGACAGCGCCUUCAUGGAGCCGAGGUACCACGUCCGUCGAGAAGAUCUGGACAAGCUCCACAGAGCUGCCUGGUGGGGUAAAGUCCCCAGAAAGGAUCUCAUCGUCAUGCUCAGGGACACUGACAUGAACAAGAGGGACAAGCAAAAGAGGACUGCUCUACAUUUGGCCUCUGCCAAUGGAAAUUCAGAAGUAGUACAACUCCUGCUGGACAGACGAUGUCAACUUAACGUCCUUGACAACAAAAAAAGGACAGCUCUGAUAAAGGCCGUACAAUGCCAGGAAGAUGAAUGUGUGUUAAUGUUGCUGGAACAUGGCGCUGAUGGAAAUAUUCAAGAUGAGUAUGGAAAUACCGCUCUACACUAUGCUAUCUACAAUGAAGAUAAAUUAAUGGCCAAAGCACUGCUCUUAUAUGGUGCUGAUAUUGAAUCAAAAAACAAGUGUGGCCUCACACCACUUUUGCUUGGCGUACAUGAACAAAAACAGCAAGUGGUGAAAUUUUUAAUCAAGAAAAAAGCUAAUUUAAAUGCACUUGAUAGAUAUGGAAGAACUGCCCUCAUACUUGCUGUAUGUUGUGGAUCAGCAAGUAUAGUCAAUCUUCUACUUGAGCAAAAUGUUGAUGUAUCUUCUCAAGAUCUAUCUGGACAGACGGCCAGAGAGUAUGCUGUUUCUAGUCAUCAUCAUGUAAUUUGUGAAUUACUUUCUGACUAUAAAGAAAAACAGAUGCUAAAAAUCUCUUCUGAAAACAGCAAUCCAGAACAAGACUUAAAGCUGACAUCAGAGGAAGAGUCACAAAGGCUUAAAGUCAGUGAAAAUAGCCAGCCAGAGAAAAUGUCUCAAGAACCAGAAAUAAAUAAGGACUGUGAUAGAGAGGUUGAAGAAGAAAUAAAGAAGCAUGGAAGUAAUCCUGUGGGAUUACCAGAAAACCUGACUAAUGGUGCCAGUGCUGGCAAUGGUGAUGAUGGAUUAAUUCCACAAAGGAAGAGCAGAAAACCUGAAAAUCAGCAAUUUCCUGACACUGAGAAUGAAGAGUAUCACAGUGACGAACAAAAUGAUACCCAGAAACAACUUUCUGAAGAACAGAACACUGGAAUAUCACAAGAUGAGAUUCUGACUAAUAAACAAAAGCAGAUAGAAGUGGCUGAAAAGGAAAUGAAUUCUGAGCUUUCUCUUAGUCAUAAGAAAGAAGAAGAUCUCUUGCGUGAAAACAGCAUGUUGCGGGAAGAAAUUGCCAAGCUAAGACUGGAACUAGAUGAAACAAAACAUCAGAACCAGCUAAGGGAAAAUAAAAUUUUGGAGGAAAUUGAAAGUGUAAAAGAAAAACUUCUAAAGACUAUACAACUGAAUGAAGAAGCAUUAACGAAAACCAGUAUUUAAGUACAGUGGACAGCUUAGGAUUUUGACAACUGAGAAUGCUCAGUUCUGAACUGGAGAAUGUAAGACACAACUAGGAAACACUGGAAAUGGAAAUUCAAUCAUGUCAUUGUAGACUGACUACUGCUCUACAUGAUUGUGAUCAAAGUCAGAUAGCUGAAAGGGACUUCUUUCCAGAGAACAAACAUCAACAGGUUUAUUUACAGGAGAAAAUGAAUUCUUAUAUAUCUCACCUAAAAGAUAACAGUGAGAUUCUUUCUGAACAACUCUAACGCUGACAGUAAAAUUAACAACCUAAAAAUUAAGCUCCAUCACACAGGAUAAAUUCUGAGAGAAAAGAUGAGGCAGGCCACCAUCUUUCCUGUUUGGGCAACUUAGUCAUUCCAGCGUGCGGGCUUUGGAGAGUACAAACUCACCAGGGACAGAAGAGAUCCUGUGGCAUAGCACAGCUGCUUUACCAAAUCAUGACCAGAAUGCUUCUGUAAGCAGGCCCCUGAUCCUGUUCCUCGUCACUGGACAGGAUCUCCCACCUGAGGCCUCCAGCUACACCCACCAGUGUUCCCUGGCCAAUGGAGAUUUGAAACCUUCCUGGGACAGAGUUCCCAGAGAGAGGGGUGGGCCAUGA